AGGUGCGCGGACACAGAAGCGUCUAAGCACAGCUUCCUCCUUGCCGCUCCGGGAAGUGGGCAGCCAGCCCAGGAACCAGUACCACCUGCACCAUGGGGCUGUCCCGGAAGGAGCAGGUCUUCUUGGCCCUGCUGGGGGCCUCGGGGGUCUCAGGCCUCACGGCACUCAUUCUCCUCCUGGUGGAGGCCACCAGCGUGCUCCUGCCCACAGACAUCAAGUUUGGGAUCGUGUUUGAUGCGGGCUCCUCCCACACGUCCCUCUUCCUGUAUCAGUGGCUGGCGAACAAGGAGAAUGGCACGGGUGUGGUCAGCCAGGCCCUGGCCUGCCAGGUGGAAGGGCCUGGAAUCUCCUCCUACACUUCUAAUGCUGCACAGGCUGGUGAGAGCCUGCAGGGCUGCUUGGAGGAGGCGCUGGUGCUGAUCCCAGAGGCCCAGCAUCGGAAAACACCCACGUUCCUGGGGGCCACGGCUGGCAUGAGGUUGCUCAGCCGGAAGAACAGCUCUCAGGCCAGGGACAUCUUUGCAGCAGUCACCCAGGUCCUGGGCCGGUCUCCCGUGGACUUUUGGGGUGCCGAGCUCCUGGCCGGGCAGGCCGAAGGUGCCUUUGGUUGGAUCACUGUCAACUACGGCUUGGGGACGCUGGUCAAGUACUCCUUCACUGGAGAAUGGAUCCAGCCUCCGGAGGAGAUGCUGGUGGGUGCCCUGGACAUGGGAGGGGCCUCCACCCAGAUCACGUUCGUGCCUGGGGGCCCCAUCUUGGACAAGAGCACCCAGGCCGAUUUUCGCCUCUACGGCUCCGACUACAGCGUCUACACUCACAGCUACCUGUGCUUUGGACGGGACCAGAUGCUGAGCAGGCUCCUCGUGGGGCUGGUACAGAGCCGCCCGGCUGCCCUGCUCCGUCACCCGUGCUACCUCAGCGGCUACCAGACCACACUGGCCCUGGGCCCGCUGUAUGAGUCACCCUGUGUCCACGCCACGCCCCCGCUGAGCCUCCCCCAGAACCUCACAGUUGAAGGGACAGGCAACCCUGGAGCCUGCGUCUCAGCCAUCCGGGAACUUUUCAACUUCUCCAGCUGCCAGGGCCAGGAGGACUGCGCCUUUGACGGGGUCUACCAGCCCCCGCUGCGGGGCCAGUUCUAUGCCUUCUCCAACUUCUACUACACCUUCCACUUCCUGAACCUCACCUCCAGGCAGCCCCUGAGCACGGUCAACGCCACCAUCUGGGAGUUUUGCCAGAGGCCCUGGAAACUGGUGGAGGCCAGCUACCCUGGGCAGGACCGCUGGCUGCGGGACUACUGUGCCUCAGGCCUGUACAUCCUCACCCUCCUGCACGAGGGCUACGGGUUCAGCGAGGAGACCUGGCCCAGCCUCGAGUUCCGAAAGCAGGCGGGCGGUGUGGACAUUGGCUGGACACUGGGCUACAUGCUGAACCUGACCGGGAUGAUCCCGGCCGAUGCGCCGGCUCAGUGGCGGGCAGAGAGCUACGGCGUCUGGGUGGCCAAAGUGGUGUUCAUGGUGCUGGCCCUGGUGGCGGUGGUGGGGGCUGCCUUGGUCCAGCUCUUCUGGUUGCAGGACUAGUGGGAAGGCGGAGGUGGGCCCCCACAGAGCCCACAGGCAGCUGCGUCCCGGAUGCUGGAGGCUUCCUGAGCCCUGAGCGCCGUGGGGCCUUGCUCUGUGGCUCUGCCCACGGUCAGGUGACAGCCACCUCCAGGGCACCGUCAGGGUGGUGCUGGCCACAGAGGCUGCAUGACCUCCCCUCCCGGCGUCCCUCCCCCAACCUCCUUCCGCAACUGGGCUUCCAGGGCCGUAGGUGCCUUUCUGCACACAGGCCGCCAGGACUCGUGGUGUCUCCAGGCUGUGUGACUGCAGGGCCACAUGCUGCCUGCAAACAGGGCAAGACCACGGAGGCACAGGGGUCCUGCUCCUGAUGGGGCCUCAGGAGGGGCGGAGAGGGGUGGAAGGGAGGGAGCUGCCCCACCUGGACCCCCGCUCUCCCUGCUGUUGUCUGAGCAGAUGGAUGGAGUCCAGGCCUGGGGGCUUCUGCUGGGCCAGCCCGGCCUCCCACACCCACUUGGAGGGUGAGACUGCAGUGGGGGUUGUUUUUAUUAAAAGCAUCAUGGACACAGCA